AGUUUUCCAGUUAUAGCCACGUUGGCACCUCUUGAACCUCUGUGGCCGUUAGCACGGUUUUCUGCCCGCGUGCCCGAGAAACCAACGGAUUAGAAGGACUUUUAAAGAUGUGUGAGGAAAGAGCUCACCGCUGAAGAAGGCUGCUGCAUCACUGAACUUCUUAUCACUAACAUAGCGAGAUUUUAGUUUGGACGAAUUUGAGGUUAUAGGGGAGAUAGCGAUGGCAGAAGACUAGGUGGAAAUGGCACAUCUAGGUUGGCUGCAGUCGAAACGGUUUGAGCGUGGUCGCUGUGGCUCAUCGUCGGCACCAAUUAACGAAGCGAUGACAUCUGCGUUGUUAGGGGUUUCUUAAACUGAGUUGGUAGAAAUGCGAAGCGUCAGGGUUCCCGCCGGCUUCGAGCCUUUCUUGGCGUAUUUGUAUCUUGAGCUGAUUUCUGCGUCAGCCCACAUCUCGCUCUGAUCCGCACGCCCCCCGGGUUGUUUUGCAGUAGCAGUCUCAGCCCUCUUCUCGUCUCAUUCCCAAAUCGUAAUUUCAGUUCACAGCUUUUUAUCUAUAAUAGCUUUAUCAACUCUUUUUCCGAUGCUCUGCACCAGAUCUCUUAAAAUAUAAAAUUACCUUGCAAGGUAUUGUUUGGAAUACACGGUAUUUUCAUGAAGACAACUAUUAAUAGAAAAAUCAGAGUCCAGAACUAUGGUUCUCCAUUUCUGGUAUACUGGUUUGCAGAAGCCUUACAUUAAGAUUUCAUAAAUGAUUGUUUUGCUGUUAAGUGCAACAACAUCACAGUAGAGCUACAUAAAGAUUGAAAGGAGAUAUUUUAUCAAGUGGCACCAGAAUGGACUGAUUAAAAUAGAAUGGCCUAAUUGGAAAGAAUUUCAGGAUCACCGGUUUCUCCUGCUUCAUGGACAGGCCUUCAGUAUUUGGCAUCACCUUUACAUGGAGCACAAAGAUGAUGAUGAUGAUGAUGUGUCUUUUGCCAAAUGGAUGAGCAGCUUCUGGGGCCACAGCUGGAGAGAGGAGGAUCAGAGAGGACUCCGGGAACGCCACCGACUGCAAGCCACCAGUCACAGGAAAACCUCCCUGCCCUGCCCACUUCCUGUGCUUCCCAGAAUUCCAUCAUCUGACUGCCAUCCUAGAAGGCAUUCUCAUGAGGACCAAGAAUUUCGAUGCCGUAGCCACGUACGGGAUUACAGAAAAUACUCAGAGGAUGGGUCAUUCAAGGAGCCACUGGAAUCAAAAGGAAGAUCCCAUUCCAAAAUUGAGAAAUUUUCAGAGUCCUUUGAACGGCAACUGUGCUUUAGAACCAAGCGUUCUGCCUCUUUGGGACCUGAAAGCAGAAAGGAGAGAAAUGAAAGAGAAUGCCUGAGGAUGGAGAUAAAAUCCCGAAAGAAAGUAGAGGAAGAAAGGAGCUCUAGGAAAGAAGAGCAUGGAGAAGCACACAUGGCUCCCCUGUUUGAAAAAGGGCCUGAAUAAUACUCUGCUUCUGCCUCAUGACAUCAGAUGCUACUGUUUUGGUUUUUUUCUUUGAGCCCCAAUUCACCAUUUCAGGAUGUGGAUGGGGGCGGGGUUGGGGGUAAAAACAGCUAUAAAAAGCAACUGCAGAUGCUGACUGACUGCAGUGGGCAGGGUAUGUAGCUGCUCCAAGAUGACUUGCAUCAUACCCCAAUUACUGCUGGCAUCUUAGUUGAGAGUAUAAUCUGCUUGGUUGCCUUUUUAUGGGAAUAAAGAGAAUAAAAGGUAUUUUAAUAGAAUAAAGAAAAAUUUGAAAAUAUAAUGGAAGGUAUUUAAAGAGCCACCCACAUAGCUUCACCAACCCUUCUCACACAUCAACUCAUAAAUCAUCUUAAAUAAAAGUCAUUGGUAUGA